AAAUAAAGUAUAACGGUAAUGUUUUCUCCGCUAACCUUAAAGAUUGAUUUGAGCACCUCACUUUGAGGACCAUAGUUCCAAAACGCUGUUCAAGUAGAAGCCUAGAAUUCAAGGGAGGACACUGUAAGGAAGACCAUGGACUAGUUGCACUGGAAACAGUAACAAAAGUAAAAAUUAAGCUCACAUGUAUGUGAUGAUGUAGGUAGGGAUUUCCGCAAGGAGUGAGUGCACGAGAUAAUCCCUGGGGACCAAGGAUUCCUUCAAUUUAAUGGGCAGUUCUUGAGGCUUUGCAAAGUUUGAUUGCAGGUGUGAAGACAGUGGUAAGGUGGACAGCAGAAUGAGGAAAAAGAUGUCCAGGGGCGUGGGAGAGGGAAUGGGGACAGACAUACUGGCAGUGAUGGAGAAGUUGGGAAGAGGUGAUUUAGAAGACCGUGAGCCGCAGCAAAGGAUCUGCUUAUUGCAGUUGCGUCCGGUGUUGUUCCUGCUCCGCUUUUCUGAUUUCACCCUUUCUGGACUCUGUCUUCGUCUCCUGCCACGCCUCUUAACAUUCUAAGUCCAUGUAAAUGACAUUCUCACGUUAAGGGCUGCAAAGAAAUUGCUGAGGAGCCAGGUAAACAGGCUUUGAUUGCAAUUGCAAUCAAACCUCUGUAGCAAAUCGUACAAUUAAAACACCCGCAGGCAGGUGUGGGCGACGCCAGCAGCACACGGGGAAGCUGGGCACGUGGGGCGGAGGCAGCUGCCUGGUUUCCAUGUGUGCGCCCUUUAAGACCCGGCGGCGCGACGGAAGCGCGUGGGCAGCACGUGGGCAGCACGUGAUAGCGCUGGGCGACUCCGCGGAGCUGCACGGCCAUGGACGUGGGCGCCGACGAGUUCGAGGAGAGCCUCCCUCUGCUGCAGGAGCUCGUCCAGGAGGCCGACUUCGUCUGGACAUAGAGUUCACGGGCCUUCGUUCUAACCUGUCUGGGCCCCAGCAGAUCAGUCUUUUUGAUUUGCCAUCGGAGUGGUAUCUAAAGACCCGUCAGAGUGUUCAGCAAUUUACAGUCUGUCAGAUUGGAUUGUCUGUGUUUUCCGCUAUUGAAGGAGAGGCAAACAAGUAUAUAGCCCAUUCUUGUAACUUCUAUCUCUUCCCUACAACGUUUGGGAUUUUGGACUCAGAAUUCUCCUUCCAGGCUUCCAGUGUUCAGUUUUUGAAUCAGUAUGGCUUCAACUAUAACAAGUUUCUCAAAAACGGAAUCCCAUAUAUGAAUGAAGAACAGGAGAAGAAAAUUAGACACGAUAUCCUGACUGGGAACUGGAGAGUUCGCAGCUCUCCGGAUAAAGACCAAAUCAAGGUGGUGAUUGACGAAGUGACGCGGUGGCUGGAGCUGGCCAAGGAAGGCGACUGGAUGACUCUUCCUGGGAUCACUGGCUUCCAGGCCUUUGAGGUCCAACUGGUGCUGAGGCAGGCCCUCCCCAACAUCUGGACGGUGCUGAAAGAUGAGGGGGUGGUAGUGAAGAAAGUGAGUAAACAACAUCGUUGGUAUCUUCAGAACACCUCUUGUGACCGAGAGAGCUGUUGGAAGGAAAAUAUUCUUCUCUCAGCAAGGGGUUUUUCUGUCUUUUUCCAAAUGCUGGUGAAAGCCCAGAAGCCCUUAGUGGGACAUAAUAUGAUGAUGGACCUGCUGCACCUCCAUGAGAAGUUCUUCAGACCCCUCCCAGAAAGCUACGAUCAAUUUAAGCAGAAUAUCCACAGCCUAUUUCCUGUUCUCAUUGAUACCAAGAGUGUAACAAAGGAUAUCUGGAAGGAGAUGAAUUUCCCGAGGGUGUCGAAUCUUUCGGAAGUCUAUGAAGUCCUGAACAGUGACUUGAAUCCCACCAAGAAUUCUGGACCAGAGAUUGUUCACGCGAGCAGGUGUGAGAAAUAUGUUGAGACAAAGUGCCCCCACGAAGCCGCGUAUGAUGCCUUCCUCUGUGGGUCAGUUCUUUUGAAAGUGGCACACUUGCUUCUACAGAAGAUAUACCACAUCGACCCCGUGCCCGAGUCAUCCUUUCCUCAGUACCUUGACGUGCUGGCUCCUUACGUGAACCAAGUGAACCUCAUCCGAGCGGGGGUCCCAAAGAUCAAUUUUUCUGGUCCAGAUUAUCCCAGUAUCCGACCUCCCAUCCUCAUCCUCAGCGUCAAAAGGUGGCCUGGGGUCAGCGAGCAGCAAGUCUACCAUAAGUUUCAGAAUCUCUGCAAGUUUGAUGUCAGGCGACUCACAAGAAGCCAGUUCUUACUCCUGACCAAUAAGUUUAAGGAUGCGCGGAACAUCCUGAAGGAGUACCGGGACCACCCGACCCUGUGCAUCUCCCUGUACCGCUACUGGAGGCACUCCCCAAACGUCAACUGCCUGCUCCAAGUCUGUGGCAUAGUGACUGCCUGGGCCCUUCUCGCGUUCAUCCUUGGAAGAUCUGGUACCUGAGUGCAGCGAGGCCUCCUGCGGCCACCCUCGGGUCCCCAUGCUCUCUGGGAGGUGUGCUGGGUGUGUUCGUGUAAAUCAGAUUCUGUUUGCAGAUGGAUCUGUUUGGUCUUUUCUAGAAAUUCUGUUAUGUCCUGAACGUGAAAUUCUGUCAACACUCUCAAUGAUAAAUCAGUCCUUAGAUAUCGUA